AGAUAGCCCAGGACUCUGCGUGGACGCGCCCCGAGGGGCUGCCGCGCCAGAUUCCCAUAUCCAGGCAGCCACACUCAGAGGGUUGUAGUAGUUGUCCACCUCUGGACAGUCCCACUCAGCCCCUUCUUCACUCUCUGGGCCUCCCAAAAGACAGUCAGCCUUGUCCUCAGGCCCGCACCCAGUUGUCAGCCUCUGACUCCUCUCCCCUCAAAGGAUUCUUACCUUGGCUCCUCCUCUUAGCCCUAACCUGCCUCCUUUGCCUGUGAGUCAUGGCAGCUCCCAUGAAUGGCCAAGUGUGUGUGGUGACUGGUGCCUCCAGGGGUAUUGGCCGUGGCAUUGCCUUGCAGCUCUGCAAAGCAGGCGCCACAGUUUACAUCACUGGCCGCCAUCUGGACACCCUUCGCGUUGUUGCUCAGGAGGCACAAUCCCUCGGGGGCCAAUGUGUGCCUGUGGUGUGCGAUUCAAGCCAGGAGAGUGAAGUGCGAAGCCUGUUUGAGCAAGUGGAUCGGGAACAGCAAGGGCGUCUAGAUGUGCUGGUCAACAAUGCUUAUGCAGGGGUCCAGACGAUCCUGAACACCAGGAAUAAGGCAUUCUGGGAAACCCCUGCCUCCAUGUGGGAUGAUAUCAACAACGUCGGACUCAGAGGCCACUACUUUUGCUCAGUGUAUGGGGCACGGCUGAUGGUACCAGCUGGCCAGGGGCUCAUCGUGGUCAUCUCCUCCCCAGGAAGCCUGCAGUAUAUGUUCAAUGUCCCCUAUGGUGUGGGCAAAGCUGCGUGUGACAAGCUGGCUGCUGACUGUGCCCACGAGCUGCGGCGCCAUGGGGUCAGCUGUGUGUCUCUGUGGCCGGGGAUUGUGCAGACAGAACUGCUGAAGGAGCAUAUGGCAAAGGAGGAGGUCCUGCAGGAUCCUGUGUUGAAGCAGUUCAAAUCAGCCUUCUCAUCUGCGGAAACCACAGAAUUGAGUGGCAAAUGUGUGGUGGCUUUGGCAACAGAUCCCAAUAUCCUGAGCCUGAGUGGUAAGGUGCUGCCAUCCUGUGACCUUGCUCGACGCUAUGGCCUUCGGGAUGUGGACGGCCGCCCCGUCCAAGACUAUUUGUCUUUGAGCUCUGUUCUCUCACACGUGUCCGGCCUGGGCUGGCUGGCCUCCUACCUGCCCUCCUUCCUCCGUGUGCCCAAGUGGAUUAUUGCCCUCUACACUAGCAAGUUCUAACCCUCCUGGUCUGACACUACGUCUCUGCUUGUCUUCUCAUUUGGACUUGGUGGUUCGUCCUGUCUCAGUGAAACAGCAGCCUUUCUUGUUUACCCAUACCCUUGAUAUGAAGAGAAGCCCUCUGCUGUGUGUCCGUGGUGAGUUCUGGGGUGCGCCUAGGUCCCUUCUUUGUGCCUUGGUUUUCCUUGUCCUUCUUUUUACUUUUUGCCUUAGUAUUGAAAAAUGCUCUUGGAGCUAAUAAAAGUCUCAUUUCUCUUUCAA